CCUUUGCGGUUCCAACAUGGCGGAGCUGACGGUGGAGGUUCGCGGCUCUAACGGGGCUUUCUACAAGUCAAUUCACAAUGAAUCAAAUGUCCCCAUUUUGGAACUCUGAAGUAUUUAUAAUUGAUCUCUAUACAUAUCUACAAUCUACUGCUUGUUUCUACUUAGACUUUGACUCCAUUACUCAUUUUGCCUCACAAAGUGAGUUGGUACUUUGACAAAGGUUGGAAAGGACACUAGCCACCUGUGUGUGCACUGAAAUCAUGUACGCUUGAACAUUUGGAAUUUUAUGUCCAGCCAUAAUCCACUUGCAUAUGCACUUUGUGGAAACUGUGGUCUUCAGAACUCUGGAAGAAUGAGAAUGGCGGAGUGGAAAAGAGUCCUGGAUUUGAAGUAAACAGAUGAGAAUUCUAGGGAUUUAUCAAAGAUGUUCAUGAAGACUCCCUUACAGUUGUUUUUGAAAAUAAUUGGCAACCAGAACGCCAGGUUCCAUUUAAUGAAGUUAGAUUACCACCACCACCUGAUAUAAAAAAAGAAAUUAGUGAAGGAGAUGAAGUAGAGGUAUAUUCAAGAGCAAAUGACCAAGAGCCAUGUGGGUGGUGGUUGGCUAAAGUUCGGAUGAUGAAAGGAGAAUUUUAUGUCAUUGAAUAUGCUGCUUGUGACGCUACUUACAAUGAAAUAGUCACAUUUGAACGACUUCGGCCUGUCAAUCAAAAUAAAACUGUCAAAAAAAAUACCUUCUUUAAAUGCACAGUGGAUGUUCCUGAGGAUUUGAGAGAGGCGUGUGCUAAUGAAAAUGCACAUAAAGAUUUUAAGAAAGCAGUAGGAGCAUGCAGAAUUUUUUACCAUCCAGAAACAACACAGCUAAUGAUACUGUCUGCCAGUGAAGCAACUGUGAAGAGAGUAAACAUCUUAAGUGACAUGCAUUUGCGAAGUAUUCGUACGAAGUUGAUGCUUAUGUCCAGAAAUGAAGAGGCCACUAAGCAUUUAGAAUGCACAAAACAACUUGCAGCAGCUUUUCAUGAGGAAUUUGUUGUGAGAGAAGAUUUAAUGGGCCUGGCAAUAGGAACACAUGGUAGUAACAUCCAGCAAGCUAGGAAGGUUCCUGGAGUUACCGCCAUUGAGCUAGAUGAAGAUACUGGAACAUUCAGAAUCUACGGAGAGAGUGCUGAUGCUGUAAAAAAGGCUAGAGGUUUCUUGGAAUUUGUGGAGGAUUUUAUUCAGGUUCCUAGGAAUCUCGUUGGAAAAGUAAUUGGAAAAAAUGGCAAAGUUAUUCAAGAAAUAGUGGACAAAUCUGGUGUGGUUCGAGUGAGAAUUGAAGGGGACAAUGAAAAUAAAUUACCCAGAGAAGACGGUAUGGUUCCAUUUGUAUUUGUUGGCACUAAAGAAAGCAUUGGAAAUGUGCAGGUUCUUCUAGAGUAUCAUAUUGCCUAUCUAAAGGAAGUAGAACAGCUAAGAAUGGAACGCCUACAGAUUGAUGAACAGCUGCGACAGAUUGGUUCUAGGUCUUAUAGCGGAAGAGGCAGAGGUCGUCGGGGACCUAAUUACACCUCCGGUUAUGGUACAAAUUCUGAGCUGUCUAACCCCUCUGAAACGGAAUCUGAGCGUAAAGACGAGCUGAGUGAUUGGUCAUUGGCAGGAGAAGAUGAUCGAGACAGCCGACAUCAGCGUGACAGCAGGAGACGCCCAGGAGGAAGAGGCAGAAGUGUUUCAGGGGGUCGAGGUCGUGGUGGACCACGUGGUGGCAAAUCCUCCAUCAGUUCUGUGCUCAAAGAUCCAGACAGCAAUCCAUACAGCUUACUUGAUAAUACAGAAUCAGAUCAGACUGCAGACACUGAUGCCAGCGAAUCUCAUCACAGUACUAACCGUCGUAGGCGGUCUCGUAGACGAAGGACUGAUGAAGAUGCUGUUCUGAUGGAUGGAAUGACUGAAUCUGAUACAGCUUCAGUUAAUGAAAAUGGGCUAGUCACAGUUGCAGAUUAUAUUUCUAGAGCUGAGUCUCAGAGCAGACAAAGAAACCUCCCAAGGGAAACUUUGGCUAAAAACAAGAAAGAAAUGGCAAAAGAUGUGAUUGAAGAGCAUGGUCCUUCAGAAAAGGCAAUAAACGGCCCAACUAGUGCUUCUGGCGAUGACAUUUCUAAGCUACAGCGUACUCCAGGAGAAGAAAAGAUUAAUACCUUAAAAGAAGAAAACACUCAAGAAGCAGCAGUCCUGAAUGGUGUUUCAUAAACUGAAGAAGUUCCUAGUUUACAGUUCUUUUACAUUACAUUUACAAUAGUGCUUGUACAAGCUUGCCAAAGAUAGAAUAUGGAUCGCCAGUCUUUACAUCGCACUUUCAGUUCCUCCAUUUGGAAUUCAAAAAGGGGAGGGAUCCUGAAGAAAUCAUAUGUUAAACAUACUUUGACACCUACUGUGUUAUAAAAUAUAUCAUCAGAUGUGCCUUGAGAAUAGUAUAUGUAACAUUAAAAAAAAGUUGCUGGCUAUAGGAAAUGUUAUUUUGUUUUCAAAAUAUGGCAGAGAUGGGGGGUGGUGGGUGGGGUGGGAUCCCUAACGUAAUAUUCUUUAUGAAAGCAUUAGCUGCUUUUGUUACAUUUUUAAUAUGCAACCACUUCUUCACCUGAGGAAAACUAGAAUGAAAUGCAGUCUAAAAUAUUUUGCACUGAAUUGUAAUUUCUUCAUUAGUUUAGUCUGGAAACUGGUCUGUUUUAAUGUGUUUUUUAAAUGCUGUAUGUAGAGGAAAAUCUGCAGACCACUGGAAUACAUUUGUUAAACUCUCAUCUGCAGGGACACUGGGCGAUACUUGGCAGUGACUGUUCUACCUUGAGGCUUUGUUUGGUUUAUUUAUUAAAGUGUACAGUAUUUAAAAAUCAAACAUAGCUUUAGUUAAAACACUAAGCUGAAUUAGUCAUGUCCAUUCAGACAUAACCUGAACUACUGAAAAGAUCAAUUUCCAGAAGGUUUAUUCUGUAUAAACUACAUGUUAGUCUUCAGUAGAGUAUCUUUUUUUUUUCCUUUUUUUUUUUUUUAUUUCGGUUGUUUGAUGUGCAAUAUGUUUUUGUAUGCAGGUAGUAAAUAAACUUUGAUCUUCCAUUUGCUGAAUUUUUUUAACUUUCUACUUUUUACACCAAUUGUUGCAAAAUAGUUGGAGCUAUUAAUAGGCUUAGGAUAGUAUACUUUGCUUUUUAAAAAGCAUUUAUACUUGCUCAUAAAUAGCAUUAAAAUGUCAGUUGGCCAUUUAAUCAUUUUGUAAUGAAUCAUCUGAAAUCUUUACACAAGUUUAGGCUGUUAGAUGCAUAGGUAAUUAAUAAUACAUGUGAUAAUUAGCAAAAAAACCUAACAAAAUUCUAAUCAAAGGCAACUUUGGAAGACAAUGGGGGAUAGAAGGGAUGACAAGCAAUUUUUAAAUAAUAGGCCAAUGAUUUGCUUUAUUCAUUCUCAACUUAUUUUGAAGGCUCUCAUAUCAGUGACCAAAAAUCAGUUAUUAAACUUUAUGUAUAUAUUUUAGCCAGAGCUUAAUUUUUAUGAAGAUAAAGACAUGAAGUUUAACAAUGGACAACAGUUAGUACAGCUAAUUGUGAGGUCAAGUAAUUGUUAGACAUAGGGGAAGGCUUUGUUCCACAAUAUUAUAUGGACCACUGAACAAGAAUGACAGCCCUUUGUUAUCACUUGGCAUAUGAAAAGUGUUGUGUGCAUAGUUUGUGUUAAUUUUUUAUGUGCAUAAAAAUGUGAUUUUAAUUUAUAUGCUCUGAAGGAUAAUUCAGGGUAUAGUUAAAAAUGUACAAUGUGCCAGUUCAGUAUAUAUAACCCUAGCCCUCAAAUUAUUCUGAUUAAGGUUAAAAUGUGCUGGUAUUACGUGCUUUUUCCUGAGGCCUUCUGAUUGGUUCUUGGUAACAGAAUUUUAAAGUAAGGUGUGAGUAGUGCAACUCCUGUCCUUUAUAUAUAAAGAUAUCAAGUAAUUUCAUGUCCUGAUAUUUAAAAAAAUUACCCACAAAUGUGUUUUUUUAAAUCGAUCAAAGCUAGCAACAGGUUAAAUUGUCUCAGUUCUCUUACAUAAUUGGGUUAAAAAUUAUAAGGUAUUAGAAGAAUUUUAAUUAAUGCCAAAUUGGUAAAUAUGGUGUAAAAAAAAAAAAAAAGACUUUUCAUUUUCUCCCACAUAGAAUAGUCAGAUAUAUUAAACAUCCCUUUUCCAUAAAGAUGGUUUCAAUGGGAAUGGAAGAAACAAAAUCUUAAAAGAGUGAGUAUAGCUGAACCAAUUCUUCAUUCUAGCAAUAACCACACUAAGUUCAUUACUUUACAAAUGACUAAACCCAAUGUCUUGUCCUUUAAAAAAUAUAGGUAGUGCAGAAUUGUGAUAAAUACGCAUUUGUUUUUUUAGAGAGCCCCACUCCCCAAAGGGUAGCCAUUAAUUCAGGUAGCCUUUUAAAUGUAUUUGAGAGGGUUCCGUCUUUUUGGCUGCUAUCCUAGUUAGGUGAGAUGUUGCUAUGGGAAGAACUUGCCACUAUACACUAAACAGACACUUAAGCAAAAGAUGUAUUCUGGAGCCUGGCACAGUAGCUUAUGUCUUUGGUUCUAGCUACUCAGGAGCCUGAGGUGGGAGCAUCAUUUGAACUCAGUUCUGGGCCACUGAGACCCUCUUUAAAGAGAAGGAAAAAAAGGUAUUCUGGAAGAUCUUGUGCAGUUGCAACAAUGUUUCAGCAUAUAUAUGUGAAUUCAUAUAUGACACCUGAACGGAAUCAUGAAGUAACAGCUGAGAUUAUAUGGUGGCAAAAAUGACCUGCUUUUCCUGAAGCUUUGGGAGGCCUAGGAUUCUUGCUUUAGGCAUCACCUUUGUUAAGCCUUAAAGGGGGCUACAACUUGUGCAAAAUGGUGUCUCUGGUAACACUUCAGAAAUAAUUGGCAAAAGUGUAAUAGGAAUACACAAAUCUUUAUUUUGAAAUAAUCUUGUAUUUUAAUGUGGAAUUAGAAGCAGCACAUCAAACUGGUGAGUUCACAGAAACUUACCUGAGAUGAUGCUGGGUUCCAUUGCUGUUGUGCUAAGUCACGUAUUUUUGUAGCUGCUGUUAGCUGUGUCUAGCGUUUUGUAACCUAAGGAGGGUCUUAUAGAAGUUGGUAUGUUAACUAAAUCUUGGACUGGGAAACAGCACCAUUUGUAUCCUCUGCAAACAGAUUUACGCUUUUGAGGCUCAAACCAACUAGUGUUCUCAUGGGCUGUUGCCUAAGGACAGAUAAACAUGGAAAACAGGCUAUGUCCAGGGACAGAUGAUUGGUGGUUAAGAAUUACAGUAAAGGAAAAUUACACCUGGAUUUUCUUCUGUAAAGUUUCAAGGAACUUGGAUUUGAACUGUGAAUCUACUGUUUUGGCAAAAAAUCUCAAAGAAAAGGAUGUUUGUUACUGUCUCAGUCUUCCUGUCUUUGCUACACGAUUUGGAUCCCUUACGCUUUUUCGUUAAGAAUAUCUGUCUGCUAUAGUGAAUUUGCUAGCCCCUUAUUUUUUUUUUUAAUUUUAGUUCUUUAUUAGAACGUGUACUUGAAUGGACUGUAGUUGCUCAUAACCCAUGUUAAUCUCUGAUAGUAUUUGGGUUUUAUUUCAGGAGCUUUUGCAAUAAAGCAGUAACUGCAAUCUGCUAAAGUCAGACUGUUAGCAAGUGGUGUUAAAACUGAUUUAAGUCCAUUACACUGAACAGUAGGAAAUUACCACUUUUGUAAGGCUCAAAAAUGAUCAACUAUUAACAGUUUCUUAUGGUUCAGUCUAAUUACAAAUUUUUAAAAAGUUUAUCAGUGUAUCAUUUCAGAUUCAUCUGUAUCUUCUGUAAUAUUAUUUCCAGUACUGAGGUAAGGUACACAAAAAUUCCCCUGGAAAAACUAUAUUCUAGUUUUGUAAGAUGAUUUCCCACAGUCCAUUUGCUUAUUUCUUCCUUUGAUAAUUCAAAAAGAUGCUUUAGGUAAUGGUACAGAAUUAGAAGCUGCUAUUUUAGCUCUAUUAACUUUUUCUCUAUGGUUUCAAUUUUAUCCAACCAGAGAGGGCUGGCCUAGUUGGUAUCUUUAAGGCCCUUCCAGUAGUAAUUUGAGUCUAGUCACAUGUCAGACCCUGAGCAACACCUAACCAAAUGCCCAAGUAUUCUCAUAAGGAGUAUGCUGAAUUUAAGUGGUGUUUGUUUUACAUAUGUAUCCAUCCCAGACAUUUUCAACUAUGCUGAAUGCAAUCUAUAAGAUAUUCCAAACAAGGACAAAGUAAUUUUUCACAAGUCUUACAGCCCCACUAUUAAGUAUGCUACUAAUUAGCUUCUUGAAUUUCUUUGUAUUUCAGUGAUUGGGAUGUUCUUUUUUUUUGGGAAAGUUUUUUUACCCCUUUGUACCCUCUUAAUUGGAUUAACUGUAAAAUGUACAUAUUAAUUUUCUAGUUUUAGAGACCAUUUUCAUUAAAAAUAUUUUCCAAUAGUUUUUCUAGAUAAACAAUUUAUACUUAAUUGUUGCUUGGUUGCUUACAUUUCAACCUCUAGGCUUCCUUUUUCAGCUAACUUGGCUGUCUUCAGGUUGUAAAGAAAAAUGUAAACAUAUAUUUGAAAUUUCAUUAACUGAAACUGCUGUAAGGUGUUAGCAAAUGUUAACCAUAACAGAUUAUCCCAUAUCAUUGGACUGUUCUAUUAUUGGGUCAGGAAUAAUAGGUGACACAGGAUAGAAGCUCUUCCUAUAUAUAUCUUGUUGCUAAGGCAGUAGUUGGCUCUAAGCUGAUAAACAGCACACUGUACAGCAGUCCAAAAACUAAAACCAGAGCUUAGGUCAUUCAAGUUAACUGGUACUCAAGGUUACUCAUUCCAGGAUACUUUACAUAACCAAAAACCUAGGAGAGCAUUCUACAUUGUAAUUUUUUUUUUACUUUGUUUACAUAAAAUUUACAGGGUUUUGUUUUUUUAAGCUUAGUCUGUUCUUUGACAUUGUUGAUUCAUGUUCUAAAUUUUCAUCAGAUUUAACAUGUUUGGAGGUUCUUGUGCACUCAAUGUGAACCUACUACAAGCUUCUGAACUGCAAAACCUUUUUUUUAGGUCACUGUCAACAGAAAGAUGCCUUAUAGAAUUUCUCAUGAUUGAAACAGAACUCUGCAUUCUAACCUAAAACCCCUCUAACCCUUUAAAUGAAGCAUUAUGCCUGCGUGAAAUUUUAUUUUUAGACAUUUCUGAUACUAGGUUUUCUUUACGGGGGGGCAUACAUAUUCAGUAUACUGAAUUUAUACAGCUUUCAGUGUGGCAAUAUAUUAAGAAGCUAGUUCCCUAAUUUUUCUCAGUUCUCAUUGGUUUUCCAUUUAAAUGUUUCCGUAAGUACUCUCAUCAUUUGGAAAAUACUUGAUGGCAGGAGAACUUGCUUAAAACUAAAGGUGGAGAAAGAGUUAACUUCCAGGACAACCCAUUAUAGCUCACUUCUUACCAACAAAGCAGUUUUUAUACAGCACCUUAGGACUCAUUUCUAAUGUCAACCCAGAUGGCCAGUAAAGGCAAGGGAAGAGGCUAAGUGACUCACAAAAAUCUCUGAUAUUGAGGUCUAAUGUGAAGGCUAUAGAUAGGAAUUCCCCACAAACUUCUAAUGAGGACUAAUAUGAACAGCAAAUUGGAGAAGACACCAAGGACCUAAUUUUAGUUUCACUAGCCGUGGGACCUUAGAAAAAAGACCAUUUGCUCUGGACUUUUGUUUCCCAAGCCAUAAAAUGUGGAAGAAUCUUCACAAUUUCAAGUUGGUCAUGUAUAUUUCCCUUUUACAGAGAAAGCUGAAGCCUCGAGGCUCAGAUUUACCUGGCUUCUGUUUACCUGGCUUCUGCAGAAGUUUAACUUGUAACCUACCUCUCAUUCCCAAAGUGUGUUUAAUCAUGCCGCCUUCUUUAAAAUAUAUCUGGAAGCACCAAUGAGUAAAGACAAAGGCCCCAAGCUAGAUCUGUAGAGAUAAGUACUAGACUCACAUCUCAGUACUAUCAAGGAAAACAUGCUUAGGUUAUCAGAAUUGUGAAGGCCAUAGUACAAAAAGUUAAGAGAACGGAACUCAGGAUCUGAGAAAGAUCAGCCAUUCUCAGCAUGUUGCCUUGGCUGCUUAACCUUACUAAACUUCCAUUUCCUCACAUGUAAAAUGUACAUCAUAAUAACUAGUCUACUGAGAUAAGGGAAGAAUACUUAGCACAGUGCUAGUACACUGUAAGUACUCAAAUGUUACAGAUCCAAGUAUUUUGUAAGAAAAUACCAGCAAAAGAUAAAAGUUUUUUUAUGGAUCGUAUUUGUAUCAAUCACCUACAUGAUCUAGAGCCCUCACAUGGAUAACAUUUAAAUGUUCAGUUUGCCUAAUAGCCUUCAAUGAAACACGGAUUCUUCUACUUAAAAAAGGUAAGCCUGGAGAAAAUAAAACUGAUUACUAUGCAAGAAAAAAAUGUGCUCUGCUGUGCUCCUUGGUAUUUUUAAGUGGUUUCCAUUGUCUUAACACCUGUCUUAAAACGGGUAUGUUGUUUGCACUGAACCCUCAAAAGUAUUUAUACCUAUUAAGUUAAAUUUCCCUUUUUAGAGUUAAUGCUUCAUUGCCUGUCGGCAUAUUAUCACUAUCUGUCUUUGAAAAAUUUUCUUUUAAGUCUCAACUAUUUCUUCAUAAAGCUCUUGUUCAGAGAAACAUUUUUUGAUUUGUCCAAUGGACUGAAAUAAAAGGUUAGUAAACCAAAA